AUUCACACUUAGGAUCUUGCCUUGAGCAGCCAAACAACUCACCACUCCUGACGCCAUGAGCUACUAUGGCAGCUAUUACAGAGGCCUGGGCUAUGGCUGUGGAGGCUUUGGUGGCCUAGGCUAUGGCUAUGGCUGUGGAUGUGGCAGCUUCCGCAGACUGGGUUAUGGCUGUGGCUUUGGAGGCAACGGAUAUGGCUACUGCCGCCCAUCAUGCUAUGGAGGAUAUGGAUUCUCAAUUCUACUGAAAUCCUACCCUGAGGACACGAUAUCAGAGGUCAUAAGAAGAUCAUUCAAUUUAACCAAAUAUUGAGUCAAACAAGGGCACACUAGAUCAAUCCAAGA